ACUCUGGGCAGCUGGGUGAGGGCCCAUCUGGGCAAGGCCCCCAGCGCCUGCCUUCUCUCCCGGGGCCCUGUGGGCAAGCCUCCUGCUUCACUUUCAGGUUUCUCGAAGUGCCUUCUUGCUCCUGUCUGUUUCCCCAUCCUGCCAGAUUUCUGUUUCUCUUGCUGGGCUUUUGGCAGUAGGGGGCUGUGUUGGUGGGCCCUACGAAGAUGCUCAGUGCUCGAGAUCGCCGGGACCGGCACCCUGAGGAGGGGGUAGUUGCAGAGCUCCAGGGCUUCGCGGUGGACAAGGCCUUCCUCACCUCCCACAAGGGCAUCCUGCUGGAAACCGAGCUGGCCCUGACCCUCAUCAUCUUCAUCUGCUUCACGGCCUCCAUCUCUGCCUACAUGGCCGCGGCGCUACUGGAGUUCUUCAUCACACUUGCCUUCCUCUUCCUCUAUGCCACCCAGUACUACCAGCGCUUCGACCGAAUUAACUGGCCCUGUCUGCUGCAGGGCCACGGGCAAUCAGGAGGACCACAUCCGCUAGAUCUACUCUCCCACUCAGCAAAGGUCCAGCCCCAGCCCUGGCCUGGCUUGACCCCCCCGGGCUGGCAUACUCCAGCCGCUGUCCCCUGGGUUCCAGCCCCAGCGCCUGGCUUCUGGUCCUGGUUGCUCUGGUUCAUCUGCUUCCACUCCCUGGGUAGCAGUGACUUCCUGCGCUGUGUCAGUGCCAUCAUCAUCUUCCUGGUGGUCUCCUUUGCAGCUGUGACCUCCCGGGACGGAGCUGCCAUUGCUGCUUUUGUUUUUGGCAUCAUCCUGGUUUCCAUCUUUGCCUAUGAUGCCUUCAAGAUCUACCGGACUGAGAUGGCACCCGGGGCCAGCCAGGGGGACCAGCAGUGACUCUGGGGCUACCUGGCUCCUAGGCCCAGCCAGCCAGAGAGGACAGUGGAGCCCAGACACGUCUCCUUGGGAUUCACUAGCCCCCAGCCCGCCAAACCCCACCCCAGCCCUACACAGCAGUCUGGCCUGAGACGUCACUGGGGACUUAUCUGUGGAGCCUGGUGCUCCAGGAUGUGGCUUCUCAUGAAGCUCUGGCCAGAGGAGGGGAACUUAUUGGGGGAGGGGGGGUGGAGGGGAGGAAUCUGGACCUCUAAGUCAUUCCCAAAUUAAAAUAUUCAAAUUCUA